GCAGUCGGCGAACUGUCUGGGCGGGAGGAGCCGUGAGCAGUAGCUGCACUCAGCUGCCCGCGCGGCAAAGAGGAAGGCAAGCCAAACAGAGUGCGCAGAGUGGCAGUGCCAGCGGCGACACAGGCAGCACAGGCAGCCCGGGCUGCCUGAAUAGCCUCAGAAACAACCUCAGCGACUCCGGCUGCUCUGCGGACUGCGAGCUGUGGCGGUAGAGCCCGCUACAGCAGUCGCAGUCUCCGUGGAGCGGGCGGAAGCCUUUUUUCUCCCUUUCGUUUACCUCUUCAUUCUACUCUAAAGGCAUCGUUAUUAGUUCAUCAUAGAGAGAGCGCGGACCGUGUGCGGGCCGUCUUGACGAAAGAACCGAGAGAUGGAUGCGCUAAGGUCUAAAGAUACCUUUCUCCCUCGACUAAAUUAAGAAUUGCUGCGGCAGUUCCCAAAAGCUGAGUCCCGCUGCAGCUGCCAGGUCGCCACACUCGCCAAGCGGCGAGGGAGCGCCUUUGCCUACCAGGCCGGAGAACCCUGUUCUUCAGUCGCCUUGGCAGGGGCAGCCCCUCCUUCUGGCAAUGAUGUCAGCUGCAGAGAGGCUUGGCCCGGCCGAUGGGAAGCCGAGCGGCGAGUCCGACCCGCAAGCACGAGCAGCCCUGCCCCGCGCGCUCCCUGCGCGCAGCCGCCCUCGUGUCCCUUCGGCCCCUCCUGGGUCCUGGCUCGCAGCCCCCCCCCUUCCAGUCCCUCGCUCCUCAGAGGCGCGCUAAGGCGCCAGAGGCGGGGGUGGCCACUGCUGGCGGCCCGCCGCCGGUUUUAAACCCGGGGUUCAAACCCAGAUUUGGGGUCUUCCCUCCUCCAUUUCCUCCUUUCCUCCGCGCCCCAGCUCUCUCCCUUUUUCAGCUUGCACCUUCACUAUUCACAGUGACUUUACUUAUUUAGCAACAUUUUAGAGGGCAAGUGUUCCAGAUGCAAUAAUAGUAGUAACUGGUGUUAAAUUUCUGCUGUUUUCUCUCCCCUCGGGUGAUAAAAAAGAUGUGAAGAACGCCUCUUUAAAAAAAAAACCCCCGUGGCUGCUGCUUCGCCUGUCACAGAGCAAGCUCUCUAGAAGGCGGGGAGGGUCAUCUUUCCCACAAAAUUGUGAGGUGGGGGAGGGUUUGUAACCUUAGGCGAAAGCGCAGGCUGGGGAAUCCCCUUCACAGAAAGAAGAAACUGCAAAUUGGAAGUUGCGGAAAGGCUCUAUCCACUACUGCCAUAGGGGAGAGACCACCAUGCUCUUUAUUUAGAGACCCGCGCUCCAAAUUGGGAUGAUGCAGGAAUAGGUUUCUUUAAGACGGAAGCCCGCUGCGGCUUCCCUUUUGAGCUUGCUCUUAUAGUCCUAAGGAGCAAGCCCCUGCUUUGCCAAAUUGGAGGCUAAUCUGUUUUCCUGAUUGCGGACAAUUCCUUCUUUAGCUUUGGUAGAAGGGCCGCAGAAUGCAGUUGGAGAAGGUUGCACAGGGCAAGAGGGAGGGGCAGAGGCAGGGCGUGUAGAGGCAACUGGCGCCUGGAGCAGAAUUUACCUUCCAAAGGAAAAAAUCUUCAAGGGGUGUCGCAACAAACUGCUUACUUACUGUGUUUUGGUUUGGACGCAGGUGAGAGAUGUGGGCAAAGGGAGCAGGAGCAAAGAAUUACUCUGUUUUGUAAAAGUAGGAUUCUUCCCCCUUCCUUUUCUUCUUCCCUUUGAUGAAAAGCUUCCCUUUCAUGACGUAUAGCUGGCAGCAAACUUAAAGUUGCUGUGCGUCUGAAAUACAGGAAUGGGAAAGAAACUCCGACCAAGCAUAAAACACACUCAUUUUCUAGAGCUCAGUCAUUUGCUAAGGGUUGAAAUAAACUGUGUACCCCCACUCCCUGCCCCUUCCCCCUGGCUCCUUGGCCUUUUUGUCACCGGACUGGAUUCUGAAGGACGUCCAGGUAAUGCUGGGUUUCAGCAGCUGAAAGGCCUGGCAGAAGGGAUUGCAGGUUUCACAUUCUUCCUUCUCUUGGUAUUCAAAACUUUAUUUAUUUAUUUAUUUUUUGCGAGAUAAAAAUUCUUGAUAGAGAGCUUCCAGACUGCUGGUGGCAGGGAAGCAAUCUGGUUAAGAGAUUCAGAAAGCAGAAAAUUCUUUUUCUCUGCGCAAGCAGUCCACAACAGCCUUUAGCUAGGAUUUAUAAGAUUCUUGGUGGAGCAAGGCGAGGCACAUCGACAAGGAGAGUUUAUAUAAGCCACUGGCCUUGAGGUACAUUGAAAAAAUAUGUAUGGCAGCCACGUUUUCUUAGUGGGAAAGAAAAUUAUUCAGGGAAUGAAAUUUUGAAGGCUAAUUCUCUCCAAGAAUCUUGCUUCACAUAAUUUAAAGGAGGUGUCAUCCCUGUAUUUGUUCACUGAGGAGUCCACAAACUUUAAUUAGUCACCUACUGUGCCAGACAAUGUGCUAGGCUCUAGGAAUACAAAAGAGAGUAUGACAAACAUGGCAUGGGCCUCUUUGAGCCAUGACACUCUUAUAGAUCUAGGAUACGAUGUGAUAAAUGAUGUAAUUGAACAUAAUGGAGAGAGGAAUUAAUUUUUGUUAAGAGGUUGAGAAGAGGUUCAUAAAGGAGAGAGAGGUCUGUGGCUUUAAAAAUAGUCAUUCCUAGUCAGUGGCUAGCCAAGAAAUGUAUCUGGAAGGUCAUGACCUGCACAGAAUAAGUAAGGAAGGGCAUGAGGGCUUGGUGUCUUGUUACAAAGUUUAGAGGUAUAUGUGUGUUUUGUAGACCUAGAACAUCUUUGAAUAUUUUUUUCCAGCAAAUUCGUUAAAGUAACAACAAUAAAAUAGCCUGAGAAAAUUGGGCAAUAGAUAGCACACAGUAGAAAUAUUAUUGUUGUUUGCAUUUAAAUGAAGAAUUGAAUACAUUGAUGUAUUACAGUAGAGACUGGAAGCAAAUAUGUUAAGAAGAUAAUGUAACAUCCAGAAAAGAGGACUAAUGAAAGAAUAGGGCCUAAAGCUAAUCAGUAUAACUAAGAAAGAAAAGAAGGCUACUUUGGGGAAUAAAAUUUCUCUUUAGGCACCAUCAUGUAUCCACUCAGAUCUUUUUACUCAUCUCACUUUCCCCAUCCAGACUUCGAAAAAUUCCCCAUCUUCCAUCUAUCCAGUAAACUCCCUUUGUCCUGGGGAGACCCCCACUCCUUCAGCCACUUUCAAGCACAUUCAUCUUCACCUCACCCCAUUUUCUACACACAUCCCUGCAUCAUCUCUGAACCUUACAUCAUGUAACAUUUUACCCACUUCAGCCUUCUUUCUACAACCAGUUAGAGCCUCUUAAUCUUGUCUUUUUCCUCCCUUUAGGCACUAACAAAUAGCUCUAUCUUGCUUCUUUUUCCUCCUCUAAGUCAGGUAUUCCCCGCCCCUUUCCCAUGCAUUAAUUAUCCUGCUAAUUUGUCCAUUCAUUUCCCCCUUUUACAUCCUCCUCCCCCUUAGCCACCUUGCAUUCUCCUAUCUUUCAUUGACCUCAAAGAAGCUAAGGGGAAAGAAAAGCCACUCUACUUUAAACUUGCUUAGAUUUGCCAAAUUUUCAUCAUCAAGGUUUCUUCCUUUCUGUGUCUUUUGCUGUUUUAGUUCACACAAGACUUUUAGUGGAAUUCCUUCAAUUUGUUAUAUAUUUUUAUUAUGCCUGCAAAUGUCUGUUUUCCUUUGGUUGUGGCUGGGGAUUCAAAUAUUUUACUUUGGGGAGUAUUUCCAACCUUUCUGAAGUUCUCACUGACACACUCCUGACACUGUUUCGCUGCAUCCCAUCCUUUCUGCUGUAUUCUCUUCCCAUGGGUAAUUCCUUUUAUAUUUUCAGUGAAAUUCUUUCUUAUUUUUAUUCCCUCCUCCCCCCCUCCUCCUUUUUUUCUUUUUGCUUUGUGGGAUUGGUACAGUGGCUCAAGUUUAAAUAUUUUGAGAAGGGACCCCCCUCAGCAGACCCCCUCAGCCCACACACAGGAUUUUAAAGCCUGUGUCAACGUGUGUUCAUGUCAACAUACAGUUACCAAUCUUCAGAGGCAAAGGAACCCCUGUUUGUUUUAUUUUAACUGCACUCUUAGAAAAUUCUUUUUCUGUGUGUAUGGUAAAGGUGCAAUUCUCAUAUCGUUGUUCUCUCUACAUUCAGUGGAAUUGAUUCAACAUCGCUGGGAAUUGGGAAGGGAAGAAAGAGUAUGCUGUAAAAAUACAUUUUUCAUCAAAGACAUAUAUACAUGCUACGUUUGGGAAAAAUAAAAUACUUGGGAACAUUUAAUUGGAUUGACUUUAUAUUACAACAUUCCAAAUUACAUGUCAUUGUCUGAGCAGAGUUCUAUUAUUUGAAGACUUUAUUGAUCAUUCAGUGUCCAGAAUGAAGAAAACUAGAGGGUGCUUAAAAAGUACAGAUCAACUGGAUGGAUGAAUGGAUGGAAGAGGAUGGAAUAUCUUAACAAAACACAUUUUCCUUAAGUAAAUUCAUGCAUACUCCAAAUAAAAUACAGAAUGUGAAGUAUCUCUGAACUGUGCUGUUGAAUAUGGUAGCUACUAGCUACAUAAAGUUCUAUUGGAUAGUACUGCUCUAGAAAUUUCUGCUGGAGGAAUGGAUGAGAGAAACACGUCUAUGGAAUUCGAGGGAGAUCAUAAUAACGAAUAAUAAGGCAUAGGAUUACCACUUCCCAUAUAAAAAGAAAAUCCUGUUGUGAAUAAGAAGGAUUCCACAGAUCACAUACCAGAGCGGUUUUGCCUCAGCUGCUCUCAACUUUGUAAUCUUGUGAAGAAGCUGACAAGCUUGGCUGAUUGCAGUGCACUAUGAGGACUGAAUGACAGUGGGUUUUAAUUCAGAUAUUUCAAGUGUUGUGCGGGUUAAUACAACAAACUGUCACAAGUGUUUGUUGUCCGGGACGUACAUUUUCGCGGUCCUGCUAGUAUGCGUGGUGUUCCACUCUGGCGCCCAGGAGAAAAACUACACCAUCCGAGAAGAAAUUCCAGAAAACGUCCUGAUAGGCAACUUGUUGAAAGACCUUAACUUGUCGCUGAUUCCAAACAAGUCCUUGACAACUACUAUGCAGUUCAAGCUAGUGUACAAGACCGGAGAUGUGCCACUGAUUCGAAUUGAAGAGGAUACUGGUGAGAUCUUCACUACCGGCGCUCGCAUUGAUCGUGAGAAAUUAUGUGCUGGUAUCCCAAGGGAUGAGCAUUGCUUUUAUGAAGUGGAGGUUGCCAUUUUGCCGGAUGAAAUAUUUAGACUGGUUAAGAUACGUUUUCUGAUAGAAGAUAUAAAUGAUAAUGCACCAUUGUUCCCAGCAACAGUUAUCAACAUAUCAAUUCCAGAGAACUCGGCUAUAAACUCUAAAUAUACUCUCCCAGCGGCUGUUGAUCCUGACGUAGGCAUAAACGGAGUUCAAAACUACGAACUAAUUAAGAGUCAAAACAUUUUUGGCCUCGAUGUCAUUGAAACACCAGAAGGAGACAAGAUGCCACAACUGAUUGUUCAAAAGGAGUUAGAUAGGGAAGAGAAGGAUACCUAUGUGAUGAAAGUAAAGGUUGAAGAUGGUGGCUUUCCUCAAAGAUCCAGUACUGCUAUUUUGCAAGUAAGUGUUACUGAUACAAAUGACAACCACCCAGUCUUUAAGGAGACAGAGAUUGAAGUCAGUAUACCAGAAAAUGCUCCUGUAGGCACUUCAGUGACACAGCUCCAUGCCACAGAUGCUGACAUAGGUGAAAAUGCCAAGAUCCACUUCUCUUUCAGCAAUCUAGUCUCCAACAUUGCCAGGAGAUUAUUUCACCUCAAUGCCACCACUGGACUUAUCACAAUCAAAGAACCACUGGAUAGGGAAGAAACACCAAACCACAAGUUACUGGUUUUGGCAAGUGAUGGUGGAUUGAUGCCAGCAAGAGCAAUGGUGCUGGUAAAUGUUACAGAUGUCAAUGAUAAUGUCCCAUCCAUUGACAUAAGAUACAUCGUCAAUCCUGUCAAUGACACAGUUGUUCUUUCAGAAAAUAUUCCACUCAACACCAAAAUUGCUCUCAUAACUGUGACGGAUAAGGAUGCGGACCAUAAUGGCAGGGUGACAUGCUUCACAGAUCAUGAAAUUCCUUUCAGAUUAAGGCCAGUAUUCAGUAAUCAGUUCCUCCUGGAGAAUGCAGCAUAUCUUGACUAUGAGUCCACAAAAGAAUAUGCCAUUAAAUUACUGGCUGCAGAUGCUGGCAAACCUCCUUUGAAUCAGUCAGCAAUGCUCUUCAUCAAAGUGAAAGAUGAAAAUGACAAUGCUCCAGUUUUCACCCAGUCUUUCGUAACUGUUUCUAUUCCUGAGAAUAACUCUCCUGGCAUCCAGUUGAUGAAAGUAAGUGCAACGGAUGCAGACAGUGGGCCUAAUGCUGAGAUCAAUUACCUGCUAGGCCCUGAUGCUCCACCUGAAUUCAGCCUGGAUCGUCGUACAGGCAUGCUGACUGUAGUGAAGAAACUAGAUAGAGAAAAAGAGGAUAAAUAUUUAUUCACAAUUCUGGCAAAAGAUAAUGGGGUACCACCCUUAACCAGCAAUGUCACAGUCUUUGUAAGCAUUAUUGAUCAGAAUGACAAUAGCCCAGUUUUCACUCACAAUGAAUACAAAUUCUAUGUCCCAGAAAACCUUCCAAGGCAUGGUACAGUAGGACUAAUCACUGUAACUGAUCCUGAUUAUGGAGACAAUUCUGCAGUUACGCUCUCCAUUUUAGAUGAGAAUGAUGACUUCACCAUUGAUUCACAAACUGGUGUCAUCCGACCAAAUAUUUCAUUUGAUAGAGAAAAACAAGAAUCUUACACUUUCUAUGUAAAGGCUGAGGAUGGUGGUAGAGUAUCACGUUCUUCAAGUGCCAAAGUAACCAUAAAUGUGGUUGAUGUCAAUGACAACAAACCAGUUUUCAUUGUCCCUCCUUACAACUAUUCUUAUGAAUUGGUUCUACCGUCCACUAAUCCAGGCACAGUGGUCUUUCAGGUAAUUGCUGUUGACAAUGACACUGGCAUGAAUGCAGAGGUUCGUUACAGCAUUGUAGGAGGAAACACAAGAGAUCUGUUUGCAAUCGACCAAGAAACAGGCAACAUAACAUUGAUGGAGAAAUGUGAUGUUACAGACCUUGGUUUACACAGAGUGUUGGUCAAAGCUAAUGACUUAGGACAGCCUGAUUCUCUCUUCAGUGUUGUAAUUGUCAAUCUGUUCGUGAAUGAGUCAGUGACCAAUGCUACACUGAUUAAUGAACUGGUGCGCAAAAGCAUUGAAGCACCAGUGACCCCAAAUACUGAGAUAGCUGAUGUAUCCUCACCAACUAGUGACUAUGUCAAGAUCCUGGUUGCAGCUGUUGCUGGCACCAUAACUGUCGUUGUAGUUAUUUUCAUCACUGCUGUAGUAAGAUGUCGCCAGGCACCACACCUUAAGGCUGCUCAGAAAAACAUGCAGAAUUCUGAAUGGGCUACCCCAAACCCAGAAAACAGGCAGAUGAUAAUGAUGAAGAAAAAGAAAAAGAAGAAGAAGCAUUCCCCUAAGAACCUGCUGCUUAAUGUUGUCACUAUUGAAGAAACUAAGGCAGAUGAUGUUGACAGUGAUGGAAACAGAGUCACACUAGACCUUCCUAUUGAUCUAGAAGAGCAAACAAUGGGAAAGUACAAUUGGGUAACUACACCUACUACUUUCAAGCCUGACAGCCCUGAUUUGGCCCGACACUACAAAUCUGCCUCUCCACAGCCUGCCUUCCAAAUUCAGCCUGAAACUCCCCUGAAUUUGAAGCACCACAUCAUCCAAGAACUGCCUCUCGAUAACACCUUUGUGGCCUGUGACUCUAUCUCCAAUUGUUCCUCAAGCAGUUCAGAUCCCUACAGCGUUUCUGACUGUGGCUAUCCAGUGACAACCUUCGAGGUACCUGUGUCCGUACACACCAGACCGUCCCAGCGGCGUGUCACAUUUCACCUGCCAGAAGGCUCUCAGGAAAGCAGCAGUGAUGGUGGACUGGGAGACCAUGAUGCAGGCAGCCUUACCAGCACAUCCCAUGGCCUGCCCCUUGGCUAUCCUCAGGAGGAGUACUUUGAUCGUGCUACACCCAGCAAUCGCACUGAAGGGGAUGGCAACUCCGAUCCUGAAUCUACUUUCAUACCUGGACUAAAGAAAGAAAUAACUGUUCAACCAACUGUGGAAGAGGCCUCUGACAACUGCACUCAAGAAUGUCUCAUCUAUGGCCAUUCUGAUGCCUGCUGGAUGCCGGCAUCUCUGGAUCAUUCCAGCUCUUCACAAGCACAGGCCUCUGCUCUAUGCCACAGCCCACCACUGUCACAGGCCUCUACUCAGCACCACAGCCCACCAGUGACACAGACCAUUGUUCUCUGCCACAGCCCUCCAGUGACACAGACCAUCGCAUUGUGCCACAGCCCACCACCGAUACAGGUGUCUGCUCUCCACCACAGUCCUCCUCUAGUGCAGGGUACUGCACUUCACCACAGCCCACCAUCAGCACAGGCCUCAGCCCUCUGCUACAGCCCUCCUUUAGCACAGGCUGCUGCAAUCAGCCACAGCUCUUCUCUGCCACAGGUUAUUGCCCUCCAUCGUAGUCAGGCCCAAUCAUCAGUCAGUUUGCAGCAAGGUUGGGUGCAAGGUGCUAAUGGACUAUGCUCUGUUGAUCAGGGAGUGCAAGGUAGUGCAACAUCUCAGUUUUACACCAUGUCUGAAAGACUUCAUCCCAGUGAUGAUUCAAUUAAAGUCAUUCCUUUGACAACCUUCGCUCCACGCCAACAGGCCAGACCGUCCAGAGGUGAUUCCCCCAUUAUGGAAACACAUCCCUUGUAAAGCUAAAAUAGUUACUUCAAAUUUUCAGAAAAGAUGUAUAUAGUCAAAAUUUAAGAUACAAUUCCAAUGAGUAUUCUGAUUAUCAGAUUUGUAAAUAACUAUGUAAAUAGAAACAGAUACCAGAAUAAAUCUACAGCUAGACCCUUAGUCAAUAGUUAACCAAAAAAUUGCAAUUUGUUUAAUUCAGAAUGUGUAUUUAAAAAGAAAAGGAAUUUAACAAUUUGCAUCCCCUUGUACAGUAAGGCUUAUCAUGACAGAGCGUACUAUUUCUGAUGUACAGUAUUUUUUGUUGUUUUUAUCAUCAUGUGCAAUAUUACUGAUUUGUUUCCAUGCUGAUUGUGUGGAACCAGUAUGUAGCAAAUGGAAAGCCUAGAAAUAUCUUAUUUUCUAAGUUUACCUUUAGUUUACCUAAACUUUUGUUCAGAUAAUGUUAAAAGGUAUACGUACUCUAGCCUUUUUUGGGGCUUUCUUUUUGAUUUUUGUUUGUGGUUUUCAGUUUUUUUGUUGUUGUUAGUGAGUCUCCCUUCAAAAUACACAGUAGGUAGUGUAAAUACUGCUUGUUUGUGUCUCUCUGCUGUCAUGUUUUCUACCUUAUUCCAAUACUAUAUUGUUGAUAAAAUUUGUAUAUACAUUUUCAAUAAAGAAUAUGUAUAAACUGUACAGAUCUAGAUCUACAACCUAUUUCUCUACUCUUUAGUAGAGUUCGAGACACAGAAGUGCAAUAACUGCCCUAAUUAAGCAACUAUUUGUUAAAAAGGGCCCCUUUUUACUUUAAUAGUUUAGUGUAAAGUACAUCAGAAAUAAAACUGUAUCUGACAUUUUAAGCCUGUAGUCCAUUAUUACUUGGGUCUUUACUUCUGGGAAUUUGUAUGUAACAGCCUAGAAAAUUAAAAGGAGGUGGAUGCAUCCAAAGCACGAGUCACUUAAAAUAUCGACGGUAAACUACUAUUUUGUAGAGAAACUCAGGAAGAUUUAAAUGUUGAUUUGACAGCUCAAUAGGCUGUUACCAAAGGGUGUUCAGUAAAAAUAACAAAUACAUGUAACUGUAGAUAAAACCACAUACUAAAUCUAUAAGACUAAGGGAUUUUUGUUAUUCUAGCUCAACUUACUGAAGAAAACCACUAAUAACAACAAGAAUAUCAGGAAGGAACUUUUCAAGAAAUGUAAUUAUAAAUCUACAUCAAACAGAAUUUUAAGGAAAAAUGCAGAGGGAGAAAUAAGGCACAUGACUGCUUCUUGCAGUCAAGAAGAAAUACCAAUAACACACACAGAACAAAAACCAUCAAAAUCUCAUAUAUGAAAUAAAAUAUAUUCUUCUAAGCAAAGAAACAGUACUAUUCAUAGAAAACAUUAGUUUUCUCCUGUUGUCUGUUAUUUCCUUCUUUUAUCCUCUUAACUGGCCAUUAUCUUGUAUGUGCACAUUUUAUAAAUGUACAGAAACAUCACCAACUUGAUUUUCUUCCAUAGCAAAACUGAGAAAAUACCUUGUUUCAGUAUAACACUAAACCAAGAGACAAUUGAUGUUUAAUGGGGGCGGUUGGGGUUGGGGGGGAGUCAAUAUCUCCUAUUGAUUAACUUAGACAUAGAUUUUGUAAUGUAUAACUUGAUAUUUAAUUUAUGAUUAAACUGUAAUUUUGUAACAUAAACUGUGGUAAUUGCAUAAUUUCAUUGGUGAGGAUUUCCUUUGAAUAUUGAGAAAGUUUCUUUUCAUGUGCCCAGCAGGUUAAGUAGCGUUUUCAGAAUAUACAUUAUUCCCAUCCAUUGUAAAGUUCCUUAAGUCAUAUUUGACUGGGCGUGCAGAAUAACUUCUUAACUAUUAACUAUCAGAGUUUGAUUAAUAAAAUUAAUUAAUUUUUUUUCUCCUUCGUGUUGUUAAUGUUCCAAGGGAUUUGGAGCAUACUGGUUUUCCAGGUGCAUGUGAAUCCCGAAGGACUGAUGAUAUUUGAAUGUUUAUUAAAUUAUUAUCACACAAAUGUGUUGAUAUUGUGGCUAUUGUUGAUGUUGAAAAUUGUAAACUUGGGGAAGAUUAAGAAAAGAACCAAUAGUGACAAAAAUCAGUGCUUCCAGUAGAUUUUAGAACAUUCUUUGCCUCAAAAAACCUGCAAAGAUGAUGUGAGAUUUUUUCUUGUGUUUUAAUUAUUUUCACAUUUUCUCUCUGCAAACCUUUAGUUUUCUGAUGAUCUACACACACACAUACACACACACACACACACACGUGCACACACACACAUUUAAAGGAUAUAAAAAGAAGAGGUUGAAAGAUUAUUAAAUAACUUAUCAGGCAUCUCAAUGGUUACUAUCUAUGUUAGUGAAAAUCAAAUAGGACUCAAAGUUGGAUAUUUGGGAUUUUUCUUCUGACAGUAUAAUUUAUUGAGUUACUAGGGAGGUUCUUAAAUCCUCAUAUCUGGAAACUUGUGAAGUUUUGACACCUUUCCUAUAGAUAUAGGAAUGAACCAAUACGCUUUUAUUACCCUUUCUAACUCUGAUUUUAUAAUCAGACUUAGAUUGUGUUUAGAAUAUUAAAUGACUGGGCACCCUCUUCUUGGUUUUUACCAGAGAGGCUUUGAAUGGAAGCAGGCUGAGAGUAGCCAAAGAGGCAAGGGGUAUUAGCCCAGUUAUUCUCCCCUAUGCCUUCUCUUCCUAAGCGUCCACUAGGUCUGGCCUUGGAAAUCUGUUACUUCUACGGCUUCAGAUCUGAUGAUAUCUUUUUCAUCACAUUACAAGUUAUUUCUUUGACUGAAUAGACAGUGGUAUAGGUUGACACAGCACACAAGUGGCUAUUGUGAUGUAUGAUGUAUGUAGUCCCACAACUGCAAAACGUCUUACUGAAGCAACAAUCGAAAAAUGGUUCUGUUUUAAAAAGGAUUUUGUUUGAUUUGAAAUUAAAACUUCAAACUGAAUGACUUAUAUGAGAAUAAUAUGUUCAAUCAAAGUAGUUAUUCUAUUUUGUGUCCAUAUUCCAUUAGAUUGUGAUUAUUAAUUUUCUAGCUAUGGUAUUACUAUAUCACACUUGUGAGUAUGUAUUCAAAUACUAAGUAUCUUAUAUGCUACGUGCAUACACAUUCUUUUCUUAAACUUUACCUGUGUUUUAACUAAUAUUGUGUCAGUGUAUUAAAAAUUAGCUUUUACAUAUGAUAUCUACAAUGUAAUAAAUUUAGAGAGUAAUUUUGUGUAUUCUUAUUUACUUAACAUUUUACUUUUAAUUAUGUAAAUUUGGUUAGAAAAUAAUAAUAAAUGGUUAGUGCUAUUGUGUAAUGGUAGCAGUUACAAAGAGCCUCUGCCUUCCCAAACUAAUAUUUAUCACACAUGGUCAUUAAAUGGGAAAAAAAUAGACUAAACAAAUCACAAAUUGUUCAGUUCUUAAAAUGUAAUUAUGUCACACACACAAAAAAAUCCUUUUCAAUCCUGAGAAAAUUAAAGGUGUUUUACUCACAUGGAUAUUUCAACAUUAGUUUUUUUUGUUUGUUUCUUUUUCAUGGUAUUACUGAAGGUGUGUAUACUCCCUAAUACACAUUUAUGAAAAUCUACUUGUUUAGACUUUUAUUUAUACUCUUCUGAUUUAUAUUUUUUAUUAUAAUUAUUAUUUCUUAUCUUCUUUUAUAUUUUUUGGAAACCAAAUUUAUAGUUAGUUUAGGUAAACUUUUUAUUAUGACCAUUAGAAACUAUUUUGAAUGUUUCCAACUGGCUCAAUUGGCUGGGAAAACAUGGGAACAAGAGAAGCUGAAAUAUAUUUCUGCAAGAACCUUUCUAUAUUAUGUGCCAAUUACCACACCAGAUCAAUUUUAUGCAGAGGCCUUAAAAUAUUCUUUCACAGUAGCUUUCUUACACUAACCGUCAUGUGCUUUUAGUAAAUAUGAUUUUUAAAAGCAGUUCAAGUUGACAACAGCAGAAACAGUAACAAAAAAAUCUGCUCAGAAAAAUGUAUGUGCACAAAUAAAAAAAAUUAAUGGCAAUUGUUUAGUGACUGUAAGUGAUACUUUUUAAAGAGUAAACUGUGUGAAAUUUAUACUAUCCCUGCUUAAAAUAUUAAGAUUUUUAUGAAAUAUGUAUUUAUGUUUGUAUUGUGGGAAGAUUCCUCCUCUGUGAUAUCAUACAGCAUCUGAAAGUGAACAGUAUCCCAAAGCAGUUCCAAGCAUGCUUUGGAAGUAAGAAGGUUGACUAUUGUAUGGCCAAGGAUGGCAGUAUGUAAUCCAGAAGCAAACUUGUAUUAAUUGUUCUAUUUCAGGUUCUGUAUUGCAUGUUUUCUUAUUAAUAUAUAUUAAUAAAAGUUAUGAGAAAUAAACAUU